GGCCGCGGUGUCCCUGAGGUUGAGGGGACCGGGAAUAGGCUGGGGGGAGGACGGGACGGGCUGAGACUGGACGGGACCCCCGGUCUGCAGCAGCAGGUGACAGCAGCAGGGACAAUGAUAAGGAGAUUGGCCUGAAGGAGGGACCGUCCCUCCCGCGCGGAAUGCGAUGUUAAUUCUGGGGCAUUGAUGUUUUACAAUGCCUGAUCAAGAUAAAAAGGUGAAGACCACAGAAAAAUCAACUGAUAAACAGCAAGAAAUCACCAUCAGGGACUAUUCAGAUCUUAAAAGACUUCGGUGCCUUUUGAACGUCCAAUCAAGCAAACAACAGCUUCCAGCCAUUAACUUCGAUAGUGCCCAAAAUAGCAUGACGAAGUCUGAGCCCGCCAUCAGGGCGGGUGGACACAGAGCUCGGGGUCAGUGGCAUGAAUCCACAGAAGCUGUUGAACUUGAAAAUUUUAGUAUAAACUACAAGAAUGAGAGAAAUUUCAGCAAACAUCCUCAGCGUAAACUAUUUCAGGAGAUCUUUACCGCCUUGGUGAAAAAUAGACUCAUAAGCAGAGAGUGGGUUAAUCGAGCCCCAUCUAUUCAUUUUCUGAGAGUGUUAAUCUGUCUGAGGCUACUAAUGAGGGAUCCAUGUUAUCAGGAAAUACUCCAUAGCUUGGGUGGGAUUGAAAACCUAGCUCAGUAUAUGGAGAUUGUAGCCAAUGAGUACCUCGGCUAUGGAGAAGAGCAGCACACUGUGGACAAGCUGGUCAACAUGACAUAUAUUUUUCAAAAACUUGCUGCAGUCAAAGAUCAAAGAGAAUGGGUCACCACAAGUGGAGCCCACAAGACAUUAGUAAAUUUACUUGGUGCCCGAGAUACUAAUGUUCUAUUGGGUUCCCUUCUGGCUCUGGCUAGUUUAGCAGAAAGUCAAGAAUGUAGGGAGAAGAUAAGUGAACUCAACAUUGUAGAAAAUCUGUUGAUGAUUUUACAUGAAUAUGACUUGCUUUCUAAAAGACUAACAGCGGAGUUGCUGCGCCUACUUUGUGCAGAGCCCCAGGUGAAAGAGCAGGUGAAGCUCUAUGAGGGGAUACCGGUCCUCCUCAGUCUGCUCCACUCUGACCACUUGAAGCUCCUCUGGAGCAUUGUCUGGAUUCUGGUACAGGUUUGUGAGGACCCUGAGACCAGCGUGGAAAUUCGCAUUUGGGGAGGCAUCAAACAGCUUCUUCAUAUUUUACAAGGAGACAGAAAUUUUGUUUCUGAUCACUCCUCCAUUGGAAGCCUGUCCAGUGCAAAUGCUGCAGGCCGAAUCCAGCAGCUUCAUUUAUCAGAAGACUUGAGCCCUAGGGAAAUACAAGAAAAUACUUUCUCACUUCAAGCAGCCUGCUGUGCUGCCCUCACUGAGCUGGUGCUCAAUGACACCAAUGCCCACCAGGUGGUUCAGGAAAAUGGUGUAUAUACAAUAGCAAAAUUAAUUUUACCAAAUAAGCAAAAGAAUGCAGCAAAAAGUAAUCUAUUACAGUGUUAUGCUUUCAGAGCCUUGAGAUUUCUCUUCAGUAUGGAAAGAAACAGACCACUCUUUAAAAGACUUUUCCCCACAGACUUGUUUGAGAUCUUCAUUGACAUAGGGCAUUAUGUACGUGAUAUCAGUGCUUAUGAAGAAUUGGUAUCCAAGCUGAAUUUAUUAGUGGAGGAUGAACUGAAGCAAAUUGCUGAAAAUAUUGAAAGCAUUAAUCAGAACAAAGCUCCUUUGAAAUAUAUAGGCAACUAUGCAAUUUUGGAUCAUCUUGGAAGUGGAGCUUUUGGCUGUGUUUACAAGGUUAGAAAGCAUAGUGGUCAAAAUCUUUUAGCAAUGAAAGAGGUCAAUUUACAUAACCCAGCAUUUGGAAAGGAUAAGAAAGAUCGAGACAGCAGCGUAAGGAAUAUUGUUUCUGAAUUAACAAUAAUUAAAGAGCAGCUUUAUCAUCCCAACAUUGUACGUUAUUACAAAACAUUUCUGGAAAAUGAUAGGUUGUACAUAGUUAUGGAGCUGAUAGAAGGAGCCCCGCUUGGAGAGCAUUUCAGUUCUUUGAAGGAAAAACAUCACCAUUUUACUGAAGAAAGACUAUGGAAAAUAUUUAUACAGCUGUGCUUAGCUCUUCGAUACUUACACAAGGAGAAGAGGAUUGUCCAUAGAGAUCUGACACCAAACAACAUUAUGUUGGGGGAUAAGGACAAAGUAACCGUUACCUUUGAAACCAUCCAAGGAAACAGACCCCGAUUCAGUGGUACAUGGGGUGAGACACAGUCAACAUUUGCCCUAAAUACUGUCACUUGCCAAAUAAGGUCCAUAUUGUGCCAUCACAUUACAAAAUGACUCUUGAGGGAAUUUGGUAAAACUGAACUUACCCUUGAACCCACCAUUCCAGAUUUCUUGACCUUUUCAAAAACCCUUAUUUUAAUGUAAACCUUCCAUGUCCGCUUGCCUCCUCUGCUUUCAAAUAAAAAAGGAAAAGAAAAAACAAAACUCAUUUAAUUAUAGUUAAUAGAUUUCAGGCAUGGACUUUAGUACAUGACACAGAAGGUCACAUGUUCAUCUUGCAAACAAACAGGCUAUGUGAAUUUCUGUUUCUCAAGUGAUAUUUGGCACCUGCUCUGAUGAUAACAACAAGAAAAAACCUGAUUCAGUGUAAAGUUUAUCAAAGGCUCCAAGGCUCUUCAAAUGUUAUCACAGGUCAGGCAUUGCUGGGAUAGAUAUAAGAUGAAAAGCCAUGGUUUCUGCUCCCUGAGCUCACAGUCCUAUGGGGAAAACGUCUGUUAUUCACUCAGCAAUUACCUUCCUAGCUGACACAUCCUACAAGUGAGCACAGCAAGCAUGAAGGACAUAACCCCUGUCUUAAUGAAGCUUAUAAUUCUGUUACAGAGUGAUGAAGGCUAGAAUGUAUAUGCAAAAUACUGUAACAUGUAAUAAGUAACCUGAAAUUCUCAACAGCUUAAAACAGUGGCAAAAUACAGCCUAAAACAGUGGCAAAAUACAGCCUGUGGGACAAAUCAAGUUGUGACCUAUUAUUAUAUGUCCUGUGAGUUAAGACUGGUUUUUAUAUUUUUAAAUGCUUGUUGAAAAAGGAAGAAUACAUGACAAAGACCAUAUUUGUUCCAUUUAGGCAAAGCCUAAAAUGUUUACUAUCUGGUCUUUACAGAAAAUUUUGUCUGCCUCUGACUUAACAAGACUCCUAUCCUGCUAAUGCUACAUGUCCAUUAUGUGUCAAUAAGGGAGCUUCCUCUGUACUUGCUUCUACAUCCCAGAGGCAGGAAAGACAGAACAUGGGAAACCAUGCCGUGGCUCUUAAAACUUCUGUCCCAAAGUAACACAUGUUACUUCUACUCAGAUUUCAUUGGUCAAAGAAAGUCAGGUGUAGCAGGAUGUGGAUGCAUUCCUCCUCCGAGAGAAUAUGAGUGAAUAGUUAUAUAGUCUAUCACAGCUAUAUAAGCACUGGGGAAAAUGUGACUAACUGUGCCUUAGGGAUCUUUUGGUGCAGAGUUAAGCAGGAAGGGUAAGAGCAGUUAAUGCAGAGGCAUAGCACAUGCAGAGGAUAGAGACAUGAAGGAGUAUAGUGUGUCUAGGAACUAUCAAGGUGUUUGAUGUGGCAAGAGAUGAAGGAGCCUUGGUGGGUGGGGAGCUUGGUCAAAGACUUAUCCUCAGAGAUUUUUCAGACUAGAAAUUAUAUGAUCAGAUCUGGGAGGUAGAAGGAUUAUUAAAAUGGCAGGUGAGGGAGCAUGCUGGGGAAAGACUGGACCCAGAUACUCAGUUUAGGACAUGUAUCAGUUAGGAUAUGUUCAGGUGCAAAAAGCCAGACUAACGAUGGCUUAAACCAUGAGGAUAUUUAGUUAUCUCACAACAAGGGGUCUGAGAGUGAGUAGUUCCAGGGUGGGUUCAGCAGCUUAGGGUGAUCUAGGCCUUUCUGUCCUUUCUUUCCAGUAUCCCCAGCAGAUUGACUUCUCCAUAUGUUUGUCAUCUCAUAGUCACAGGAUGGUUGCCAGAGCUCCAGACAUUAUUACCAAAUUCAAAGAUGGGAGGCAAGGUGGCUGCUUGGGUAAAAUCUAGAAAAAAAAAUUGUCUUCUCCAAAUGCUGUCUCAUCUGCUUUUACUGUUAAAGAAAAUCUUCCAAAGAAGGUCUCCAUUAGCCUUCUUAUAUUGUGUUGACUGAAACCAAGUCAUGUGACUACUCCUCAUUGUAAGAGAGACUGUUGAGGUGAGCUUCCAGCCUCUAUAGUUGGAGAUGAGAAAGGGAGAGGAUUUGGUUGAUGGUUUUUGGAGAGCUGGCCCACAAUGUUUGCCACUGAAGGCUCUUGCACUUUUGUCCAGGAAAGUCAUGAUGUGGGUUUUUCCAAUGACAGAAGGAGAAGAGAAUGUGAAAAAGGGGCUCAAUUCAGCAGUUAUUUGGGACCUAGAAUUAAAAAGAUUUGUCGGCCAGUUAAUGAGAUGUGAGGUAUGAGAACAGUUGAGAAAGAGGCUGAGUUUGUGAAGAUUGCUCUGCCAUUGGCAGAGAUUUAGGUGUAAGGUUUUGGACAUGCUUAGUUAAAAUCUAAUUAUGCUCUUCUUCUGGUUAAAAUCCUUCAAGUAAUUGCCUAUAAUAUUUAAGAUAAAGUUUAGUUUCCUUAUGGCACCCAAAGCCCUUUCUUCGUAAUCUCCUCCUUGCUCCUUGCUCUGACCUCCUGGGACAGAUUGCACUUUCCUGAACAGGAUGUGGCUGUAUGCCUCUGGGACUUCUAACAUGCCAUCCCUCUGCCUGGAAUGCUCUUCCUCCCUUCUGCCACUCAGGUCAAAUGCGCUUCCUCCAGGGGGCAUCUUUGACAUCCACAUCUGAUAUGUCCAGUUUCUGGGACCCCUUAGUACACUGGGCUUGCCUGUCUCAUAGCACAUGGCACAAAGUAUUGAAAACACUGGCUUAUUGCCAUCUUCUCCUUGAGGUGAGAGAAAUGAACUUUCUUGACCUUCUUUCUCUGAUAGCACUUAAUAUUUUUAUUCACCAAAUGAAUAGAAGAAUGAAUGAAUUAAUGAGCAAAUGAACAAAAACACAUCCAGGUGGAAAUAUUCAGAAGCCAUUUUACAAAUAGGGAGCAGAGAUUGAGGUGAUACCUGGGUUUGAGAUCUCCUUCUGAUAGCCAAGAUUGUCUAGAAAGAGUGCUUAAAACAAGAGGAGUUGAAUAUUAAUGUAGAAAUUGCAUGCGCACAUGGGCAAAGGUCCAAGCAGUUCCCACUGUCAUCUUAGCAAACAGUAACUCAAAGAAAAAAUUUUACUUUCUUGAAUGCCACCAAAGUUUCAGACAUUGAAUUGGACCUACCCUGUAUUGCCAGAAUCUUCAGUAUUUUAAAUUUUUCAGAGGAUUAGAGGACUUUUAAUUGUUAUUGGUUGGCUAAACUGUGGCUGAGAAAUUUGUGUCAUUAUAUAAAAAAAAGAGUUAGUAUUGCAUUUCUGAUAGGGAACUCAAAGUCCUUAUGUGCACAUUACUCAUAUACUUACAAAACCUCCUGGUCAAAUACAUAUAUGAUGGACUCUAUUCAUGGUUUUUGUAGGUCUGUCGACAUGCCUUGCUUUGAACUUGUUCUGUGGUUUACUUCCCGUUAACCGGAUAUAGUGUCUAUAGAGUUUGAGCUGACACGACUUGAGUACUCUUAAAAGACUACAGAAUAUUGAGCCACUUGUGUUAAAUACCCUCAUAGCAACUGUUGUAAGAAGGAUCACCAUGGAAUUUUUCUCAGUCAACAGAUUGGCCUCAUGUUAGUAAGAAAGUAAGAAUAUUUUUGUCAAGUUAUCACAGUUGCCUUGUAUUGCCAUUGGGUCUCAUAACAUAAAAAGGAAAUGUCAAAGGAAAUUCAGUCAAAUCCAAUUUCUGAAGUACUUUAAAGAUUCUUACACCUUUGGUGGGUCAUUCUGCAUUUCUCAGAUUCUAUAUUUUUAAGUUGGCUACAAGAAAAAGAUAAGAAUGGGAAUUCGACAAAGUUAGAGCCAGAUGGGGUUAGUUUCCAACCCUGACAAUUGUUAUCCUUUUCUGAUGAGACAGUGAACUGGGUGAGCACAGAAGGAGACACCAAAUUUUUAUGACCUUAGGUGAAAGUUGGAAAUAGUAACCUCAUAAUUGAGGUUUAUAAGGCCAAAUAAAAACACCGAAGACUAAGGUUAAUACAGUAGAGUUCAUUUUAGUGUGUAUUUGGGAUAUGAUUUGGUUCUCUGAGAGCUUUUAACUGAAGGGGGUGGAAUCUGAUGUGUGAUGUCGUCUGGAUGAGUUGUUUUCACUCUGUGAGUUUUCCCAAAGUGUGUUUUCUGAAGAAACAUAGUGAGUAGGCAGUAGUACCUAUUUUUGUAGAGACUAAUUCAGUGGUACAGAGUACUAUGCUUCUGAUUAUGUCAUCAGCAUUUCCAGCCAGCUAAGUCUACUAAAGCCAUUGGAGCUUCAGAGGUACUGCCCUGAUCUCCAUCCUAGGCCUUUUAAGAACUAGUAUCAUGCCACACACAGUAUGUGUGUGUGUGCAUGUGUGUGUGUGUAUGCCUGCAUGUGUGCGCAUAUGUGAAAAAAAGAGAGUGCACCCCUGACUUCCCAUCCUUAUAGGAGUCUGGCCCUUGGCACUUUUAUGUAAUGUUAGAGCUAUAUGUACAGAGCUCCAUUAUUCCAACUGAAUAACCAGAAACAAACCCCAUUCUGAAGAAUGAUUUUAGAAGAGCCCUCUGUGGUUUACUUCCCAUUAACCCCAGAUACAGUGUCUAUUUGAGUCUGAGCUAAGGACAUUAGUUUUCCCAAGGAUCCAGUCUGUUGAUACACAUCUUAGAGCUAGGUAAUGUUUAUGUACCACAGAUAUGGAGUUACCUAGAAUUCAGAAAGCAUUCUUUUAUCAAGUGUUGAAUUUUUCAUCAUGAAGCUCUGUGUCAUCAUAACUCCAUCAAUAAAAUCAAGCAAAUAAUGAUGCUGUUGAGAAACAGAAGUUCCUUCCCUCUCCCUCAUCCCUGGUGGAGUCUGCACUGGAGAAGGAAGCUUUGGAGAAGUGGAAAGUGGCAUGGUACAGGGGUCCCUGGCACACCAACACCAAACACCUGCCGCCUACUCUUUGUUUAGGAAUAUCUACUUUAGACUUAAUUAGCAUGCCAUUUGUUGAAUUAGAAAUAAUUUUAAUAUUAAUAGUAGUUGGACUUCAUUUAGCUGAAGGUCAGGAAGCAGUUUGAGGGGCAGAGAUUAGAAUCUGAAUGACCUUCAGAGGAGGAAGUGUCAGUGAGACAGGGGUUCGUUGAGGGAAAACUCUGAGCAUUAUCCUGGGAAACUCCUUCCCGUCCCUCACUGACUCCUGCACUGAGAGGAUGUUACUGAUGGUCCUGUUGCUGUGGACAUUGUAGGUUAGCCAUUCCAUUUACUGAGGCAGCAGGAAAGAGUAGAGUGGUAAAUGAGCUGGAGAUCUUUAUUCUGGCCUGUUUCACAGUUGUGCUCAAGUAGACUCCUCUGUCAUUGCCUAGUAUUAUAGAGGUUUCAAAUAAUCAUUUCCCGAAAUUGUCAGGUCAUUAAUUAUUUUCAUUUUACUCAGGGAAGACAUCUUUAAGAUGAUAAAAAUUUUUAGCUAUGCUUUGAAGAAAAGGAACAACCACCCAUAGCUACAUCCCUUGAGCAUUUACUAUGUGAUAAAAGGAUAGAUAUGCAUUUUCUCAUUCAAUACUCUGAUGCCUUUUAAAGAUAGUGAAAAAGGUUUAGAGAGUUUAGAAAACUUGCUUAAAUUCCCUGUUUGUAGAUUGACAGUGUCAGCAAUGAACCAUGUCUACUUCUAGAGGUCAUCUCUUAACCAAGUCUCUCUCUACUAUUCUCUCAGAGGAAGCCAUUUCAGGUAACGAAAAAGACAUGUUUGAAAGGCACCAAGAUGCUUAUGGUCAAGUGCUGUACAAGGAUGAGUAGUUUGUUGGAGGGGACAUUUUAAUUUGGGCAAUUAUGAGAGAGGUCAGUCACCUGAACAUGGCUGCAGGGUCUUGCAUAGCCUGUCAAUAACCCCCAUUUGGCCACGCAGUUCCUCAGUAGACCAUUUUCCCUUGACCAUAGGGCCUUUGAGCAUGCCAUUUCCUCUGCCUGGAAGUCUCUUCUUCACUUUCUCCUCUUACCUAGAUAAUGUCUGCCUUCCUUCAGAUGUUAACCCAGUCACCAUUUGUCACAGAGGCUUUUCCCAAUCAGCUGUUUUCCUUAUAAUACCCUCUCUUAACCCCAUAUAUGGGGGAAGGUUAGGAAGCAGUUGGGGGGCAGAGAUUAGAAUCUGAGUGACCUUCAGAGAAGGAAGUGUCAGUGGGACAGGGAUUUGUUGAAGGUCAGUCUUCUUUAAUGAUCUUAUCACAACUGUAAGUUUACAUUUAUAUGUGUGAUUCUUUAUUUAAUGUGUAUCUACACCACUGGUCCCUAAAGUCUGUGUCAUCAUGGAUGGUUUUUGACCUGGUUAUCAUCUUAUCUUGAGUACCUGGUUCAGCACCUAGAACAUAUGCUCUUAGUGUUGGACAAAUGAGUAAAUGGACAAUCAUGAAGUCCAGAUAAGGCAGCUGGAAACUUUGUAAAAAAUAGCAAUCGGAAGACCUUCUGGUACAUAAGUGGGGGCCUGAUGUGAUGAAGGCAGGUGUUGGUAGAUUGUUUCGUUGUCAAAUACCCUGUAGGAUGGAUUAAAAGGAAAAGCUUUCUAAAGAAGUGCAUCCCCUUUUUUGCAGGAAGAGUGAGAGCCUAAGCUCCUGGCACAUUUAAACUAUAAUCAGACAAAUCAAAAGAAAGAUGCAGAUACAAGAGCUGGUGAGGGGUUGAAUAUAGCAGCAAGUGAGAAAAGGCAAAGAUUUCAAGCCCAGGAAAUGGGGAAGAUGAGAUGCCAUCUGGUUGACUGGGAUAUCCCUGAUGACUGAAUGAUGAGCCCAGUCUUGGGUGGGAAGUGGCAGGUGCUUUAUAGGGCUGGAGGUGAAACCCCAGACAAAGGCUGGGACUUUACAGCUGAAUUUGGAAGUCACUGACACAUAUGUGAUGGGUGAAAGGUUGUGAACAGCUGGGUUCCCUGUGGAUAGGGUUGGGAAUACCUUGCAUCUAUACAGUAUUUCAAACUGCUUUUCACCUAUUGUCAUGCUGUUGUUGAAACAAUCCUUUGCAAACAGUAAGGUAAGUUUUAUAGGCCAUUUUUGAAAACCAGAGAGCAAGAAUCUAGGGACUCAGCCAAAGCACACACAACUUUUCCAUCUGAAGGCUGGUAAUUGUAGGGCUAUAGUGUAAACAUGCUAUAGAAUUUAACAUUUUCUGUAUCAUUUGUCCUGUCAAAGGGGAGAAUUUCUUUGGAUCCUAUUUUUUUUUCAUAAUGUGCUGUAUGCAAAAUGUUUUCUAUUGUCAUUUUGAAUACCUGUAAUGGCACAUGAAUGCUUUUAUGAGUACAAUUUCUGAAAUAAAACAUUUUCUUCUUCUCCAAAUAUGAUCACAAAUGAGGAAAGAGUAAUAGAAACAUUUCUGUUACCACCCAGGUCUCCCAAAUGUCCAAACAAUAUUAGUUUUUGCUCAUUUUAAGAAUACCUCUCAACUCUCUGUGUUUUUAUGGAUAUCUGUCCAAGUGUCUGCUAUUAUCUAAAUUAACUGGAGUGAAUAAAAUCAUUGUAAUGCUCCUCAGUUUUUGCCUUUCAAAAUAAAUGGCAUUUUAGUAAGAAUAAGAUGACUCUUACAUAGCAUUAGAAAGAAAAGCCAAAGCAUUAUUUUUGGUUAUAAGUUGGUCAAGAAUUGUAUGCUAAAAUUAUAGUGGGCUCCCUAAAAAUAUUGAAGUUGUGAAUAUUGAAUACUUUUUUUUUUCUGUAUAGUGAUUGCUUAAUUUUAACUAAUUUUCUCCAGUACAUAAAAGGGGAAAGAUAGCAAGCCAUCUAGUUUGUGAAUAGUUGUUAACACCACCUUAUACGAUUUAGUCUUCUAAUAUGUCCUAUAUGUGAAUAGUACUAUUAGGUGGAGAGGUUAGACAGAUAGAUAGGUAGAUAGAUAGAUAGAUAGAUAGAUAGAUAGAUAGAUAGAUAGAUAGAAGAUAGAUAGAUGGAUGGAAAGAUAGAUGGAUAUACAUAUAGUUAUGCCUAUAUAUGUACAUAUACAUGUAUUAAAAGAUAUGUAUCCAUCAGUCUACAGGGAUAAGCAAUACAAAGUCCUCUCAUGGAUCUUUCAUACUAGUUAGAAAUGACAGACCCUAAAUGAAUGAAAAAAUACUAAAUAAAUACAUAAAGUAAUUUCAGAUAAUGAAAUAUGUUAAGAAUUAAAUAAAUGUAAUAGAAGAAUAUUGAAGGAGAGGACUUUUUUUUUAUAGUGUGUACUAGAAAAGUCAUUCUGAACGCCCAGAUCAUGUAUGGUCGUGUAGACCUUGUAGUAGUUUGGCUUUUAUUCUUAGUAUUUAUCAAACGUCUUUGUAGAGUUUUAACCUUGUAAGUAGUGACAAAUGAGUAAAUGGACACUCGUGAUGGCAACUUUAGAUAUUUAAAAGAUCCUUUUGGACCUGAAGUGGAGAAUUAUAUUUCAUGAGGAGAGAUGGAGGGAGGGAGUCUGUUCGGGAGGAAUAGCUCAGUAGCCUCAGUGAGACGUCACAGUAGCAUGGACGGAUGAUGGCAGUUGUAUUCAUUAUCCAUUGCUGGGUAACACAUUCCCCAGAAAUUUGGAGGGUUAAAAUAACAAAUAUUUAUUUUCUUAUCAUUUCUGAGGGUCAGGAGUCCAGGAGCAGUUUAUCUGGGUGAUUCUGACUUAGGGUUUCUCAUGAGGCUGUAGUCAAACUGUCAGCCAGGGAUGCAUCAUCUGAAGCCUGGACUGGGGCUGGAGGGUCAGCUUCCAAGAAGGCUCAAUACCAUGGCUGGCAAUGGGUUCUGGGUUUUGACUGGAGUGAGUGCCUCAUUUCUCUUCCAUUUGGCCUUUUAUCCUUGAGGGCUGCUCUUCUCUAUAUAACCUCUUCAGCAGAAUAACCUUUACUAUUCUACAUGGUUGCUGGGUUCUGAGAGAGAGUCAGUGAGCAAGAGAGAGCACAACACAAUUGGAAGCUGUAGUUUCUUUAUAACCGAACCUUGGAAGUAACAUCUCAUCCGUUCUGCUAUAUUCAGUUCAUUAGCCAUGAGUUACCAAGUCUCAUCCACACAUAAGAGAAGGACAAUUAAGAUUCACCUCCUGAAGGGAGGAAUGUUAAAGAACUGGUGAACAUUUUUCAAAACUACAACUUCAGUGGAGGUGAUGAGAGGUGGCCUAAUUCACUAUAUAUAUAAACUUUUUGUAGAAACAAUAGGAUUUUGCUGUGGUAAAGGAAAGUGAGGAACUAUAUCAGUCAGGACUCAUUCAUGAGACAGGAACAACCGAGUAAUUUUAACAGGACAAGUUUCAUGUAUUAAAAUGAUUUUUAACUAGUACUAAGAUUAACUACAAAGAGUUAAAGAUAACCCAAUAAAGAACACAGGAAUAGCAUAUACAGGUAUACCUUGGAGAUACUGUGGACUUUGUUCCAGAACACCACAAUACAGCAAAUAUUGCAAUAAAGCAAGUCAUAUAAACUUUUUGGUUUUUCAGUUUGUACACGUUGUGUUCACAUUAUGUUAUAGUCUAUUUGUGUGCAAUAGUCUAUUUGUGUGUAUUAUGUCUAAAAAGCAAUUUAGGCACAUACCUCAAUUAAAACAUAAUUCGUUGCUAAAAAGUGCUAACAAUCAUCUGAGCCUUCAGCAAGUCAUAAUCUUUUUGCUGGUGGAGGGUCAUGACUUGAUGCUGCUUACUGAUCAGGGUGGUGGUUGCUCAAGUUUGGUGUGGCUGUGGCAAUUUAAUAAAAUGAGACAACAGUGAAGUUUGCUGCAGAGAUUGUCUCUUCUUUUCACAAAAUAAAUGUCUGUAGCAUGAAAUGCUGUUUGAUAGCAUUUUACCCACAGUAAAGCUUCUUUCAAAAUUGGAGUCAAUCCUCUCAAACCCUGCUGCCUCCAUGUCAAUUAAAUUUAUGGAAUAUUCUAAAUCUUUUCUUGUCAUUUUAACAACGUUCACAGCAUCUUUCCCAGGAGUGGAUUCCAUUCCAAGAAACCUGUUUCUUUGCUCAUCCAGAAGAAGCAACUCUUCAUCCGUUCAAGUUUUAUUGUGAGAUUGCAAUGAUUCAGUCACAUCUUCAGGCUCCGAUUCUAAUUCUAGUUCUCUUGUUAUUUCCACCACAUCUGCAGUGAGUUUCUUCACUGAAAUCUUGAACCCUUCAAAGUCAUCCAUAAGGGUUGUAAUCAACUUCUUCCAAACUCCUGUUAAUGUUGAUAUUUUGACCUCUUCCCAUGAAUCAUGAAUGUACUUAAUGAUAUCUAGAAUGGUGAAUCUUUUCCAGGAGGUAAACGUUGCCCAGAUCCAUUAGAGGAGUCACUAUCUAUGGCAGCUAUAGCCUUAUGAAAUGUAUCUCUGAAUUAGUAAAAGUAGAAAUGACUCCUUGAUCUAUGGACUACAGAAUGGAUAUUGUGUUAGCAGACAUGAAAAUAACAUUAAUCUUUUUUUACAUAUCCACCAGAGCUCUUGAGUGAUGAGGUGUAUUGUCAACAAACACUAAUAUUUUGAAAGGAAUUUUUUACUAAGCAGUAGUUCUUAACAAUGGGCUUAAAAUAUUCAGUAAACCAUGCUGCAAAUAGAAGGACUGUCAUUCAGACUUUGUUGUUCCACUUAUAGACAACAAGCAGAGUAUAUGUAGCAACAUUCUUAAGGGCCCUAGGAUUUUCAGAAUGGUCAAUAAGCAUUGGCUUCAACUUAAUUACCAGCUGCAUUAGUCCUUAAUAAGAGAGCCAGCCUGUUCUUUGAAGCUUUGAAGCCAGGCAUUGACUUCUCCUCCCUAACUAUGAAAGUCCUAGAUGGCAUCUUCUUUCAGUAGAAGGGAAUUUUGUCUACAUUGGAUAUCUAUUCCUUAGUGUAGCUACCUUCAUCAACUGUCUUAGCCAGAUCUGGAUAACUUGCCAUAGCUUCUAUAUCAGAAUUGGCUACUUCACCUUGCACUUUUAUGUUAUGGAAAUGUCUUCUUCCUUAAACCUCGUGAACCAACCUCUGCUAGCUUCCAGACUUUCUUCUGCAGCUUUCUCACCUCUCUCAGUCUUCACAGAAUUGAAGAGAGUUAGGGCCUUGCUCCAGAUUGGGCAUUGGCUUAAGGGAAUGUGUUGGUUUGACCUUCUGUCCAGAUCACUUAAACUUUCUCUUUAUCAGCAAUAAGGCUGUUUUACUUUCUUAUCAUUUGUGUGUUCAGAAGUGCCACUCCACUGAGUAGCACUUUUAAUUUCCUUCCAGAGCUUUUCCAUUACAACAUGGCUGUUUGAUGCCAGAGGCCUAACUUUCAGCCUGUCUCAGCUUUGGACAUGCCUUUCUCACUAAGCUUCAUCAUUUCUAGCUUUUGAUCAAAAGUCAGAGAUGUAUGACUAUUCCUUUCACUUGAAUGAUUGGAGGCCAAUGUAUGGUUAUUAACUGGCCUAAUUUCAAUAUUAUUGUGUCUAGGGGGAUAAGGAGGCUCAUAGAGAGUGAGAGCUGGGGGAACAGCCAGUCAAUGUAGCAGUCAGGAUGCACACAAUGUUUAGCAAUUAAGUUUGCCGUCUUAUAUGCGCAUGGUUUGUAGUGUCCCAAAACAAUGACAAUAGUAACAUCAAAGAUCACUAAUCACAGAUAACCAUAACAGAUAUAAUAAUAAUAAAGUUUGAAAUAUUAUGAGAAUUACCAAAAUGUGAGAGACAUAUAAAGUGAGCAGAUGCUGUUGAAAAAAUGGUGCUCAUAGGCUUGCUGGAUACAGGGUUGCCACAAACCUUCAAUUUGUAAAAAAGAAUGCAAUAUUUGCAAAGUACAAUAAAGUGAAGCACAAUAAAAUGAGGUAUACAUAUAUAAGCAGCUACUACCUCUAGGGCUGAGGCAAACUAUACAAAGAAGGAGCAAAUUUUAAGACAGCCCCUCUCCUCAAGGGCUGAGAUCCAGACUUUGUUGGAGAGGGUAUGACUAUAGCCCACAGAUGGCAGAAAUUGCAUUGAAAUGCUGCAGGAUAAAGCUGUCAAACAGAAAGCUGCCCCUGGAAUGAUGACCAUGUUUUUCAGGAAGCCAUUUUCUGGGGUAUGAGUAGAACUCAGUAGGAAGCUGUUGGCUUGGGUGCUCCUGAGACUAACUAGACUGAGCCUGGCUAGAAUGCCGGUAGAAGUUACUGGGAAUCUACCUGUGGAGGUGUUGUGAAAACAGCUGAGAUGCCAGCAGAAUUUCAUGGUAUGUUGUCUGCUGGGGUGCUUGCAAAACUUGCCAGGAAGCUGGAUAUAGUGCCAGUGGAACUGUCUACGAAGCUGCCUCUAGGGGAAGUGAGCACCACUAAGCAUCCUGCACACUGCACAAGUGCUACAGGAGCAAGGAAAGAGAGGAAGCAUGUCAGAACCUGGAAAAGAAGAGAAGCCUCUCCUGUAGUUUCUCUUCAGCACACCCUCUACUGACAAAGCUUUACAUCAAGCCAGCUGGCGAAGGAGAGACAUUAUCAAGGUCCAGCUCCAUUAACAAAGCAGGGCAAUGAUGAAGGGUGGAUUUGAUGCUGAAAGGGAAUAAGUUGACAGCUAGCACAAGAACUAAGGAAAGUACCUAGGUCAAUGAUGGUGCCACUUACUGAGAUGGGAAACCAAGGAGGAGUUGUUUGGGUUAAGAUUGAGAAUUCUCUUUGAGUGUGUUAAUUUUGAGAUGCCUAGGAGACACUUAAGUGAAAGUUUUGAUUAUCCAGAUGAAUAUGUAAAUCUGGUGCUCGGAGAGAGGAAGGGACUAUUUCCAACAAAUGGUGCAGGAACAGUUGCAAAUCCCCAUAAAAAAAUCAGAACCUCAACCUACAUAUUGUAUCUUAUAUAAAAAUUAGCUCAGCUUGGAUCAUAGCACUAUAUGAAACUUAAAUUAUGAAACUUCUGGAAGAAAAAAAUGGAUAUAGUCUUUGCAGUAUUGGGCUAGGCAAAUAUUUCUUAGACAGCAUCAAAGCCAUAACAUGUAAAAUAAACUAAUAAAUUUGACUUAGUCAAAGUUUAAAACUUCUAUUCUUUGAAAAACGUUAAGAGAAUGAAAAGAUAAGCUGCAGACUAGUAGAAAAUAUUUGCAAAUUGUAGGCCGGGCGCAGUGGCUCACGCCUGUAAUCCCAGCACUUUGGGAGGCCGAGGCAGGUGGAUCACGAGGUCAGGAUCGAGACCAUCCUGGCUAACACUGUGAAACCCCGUCUUUACUAAAAAUACAAAAAAAUUAGCCGGGCGUGGUGGCGGACACCUGUAGUCCCAGCUACUCGGGAGGCUGAGGCAGGAGAAUGGCAUGAACCCAGGAGGCGGAGCUUGCAGUAAGCCGAGAUUGCGCCACUGCACUCCAGCCUGGAUGACAGAGUGAGACUCUGUCUCAAAAAAAAAAAAAAAAAGGAAAUAUUUGCAAAUUGUAUAUCUGACAAAUAAUUUGUAUCCAAAACUUAAAAAUAAGAAAAUAAAUAACCUAAUGAAAAAUGCAAAAAUUUGAGCAGCCAUUUCACUAAGGAAGAUACCCAGGUGCUCACUGUGCCAGCAUGUAUACUAAAAUUGGAGUGAUACAGAGAUUAGCAUGGCCCGUGCACAAGGAUGACAUGCAAAUGCAUGAAGUGGUCCAUUUCUUUAAAUGAAGAUGCCCAGAUGGCAAAUAAAUACAUGAAAAGUGUUCAACACAAAUAAGCUCUAAGGAAAUGCAAAUCAAAACUAUACUGAGAUAUCACUAUGUACCUAUUAGAAUGGCUGAUUAAACAAAAACUGACAACAUUAAAUGCUGAUGGGGAUGCAGAAGCAACUGGAACGCUCAAAUUUCUGGUGAGAGAAAAAACUGGAAAACAUUUUGACUUGGCAGUUUUUAUAAAAUCAAAUUAAACACAUGCUUAUAAUAUGAUCCAGUAAUCCCACUCCAAGGCAUUUUUCAAAGGGAAAUUUAAAAUUAUGUUCCCACAAAAAUUCAUAUGCACAUAUUGUACUUACCUGAAUCUUCAAUAGAAUGUUGACUAGGAAUGCUGAGAAUGGUGGACAUGUUUUGUUUUUGAACUUAAAAGGGAAACACUCAGUUUUUCAGGGUUAAGUAGAUUAUUAGCUACAGCUUUUUUUGGUAGAUGCUCUUUAUCAGGUUAAGAAAAUACCCAACUAUUCUUAUUUUGCUGAAAGGAAUAGAUGUUGAAUUUUGCUGACGCUUUUUGCACAUCUGUUGAGAUGAUCAUGGUUUUCCUUCUUUAAUGUACUGAUCUGGUGAACUACACUGAUGAUUUUUUAAAAUUAUUAUUUAUUUAUUUAUUUAUUUAUUUAUUUAUUUAUUUAUUUAUUUAGACUGAUUUUCGCUCAUGUUGCCCAGGCUGGAGUGCAGUGAUGUGAUCUUGGCUUACUGCAAGCUCUGCCCGCCGGGUUCCAGUGAUUCCCCUGUCUCAGCCUCCUGAGUAACUGGGAUUACAGGCACCUGCCACCACACCCAGAUAAUUUUUUUGCAUUUUUAGUAGAGAUGGGAUAUCCCCAUGUUGGCCAGGGUGGUCUCAAACUUCUGACCUCAGUUGUUCCACCUGCCUCGGCCUCCCAAAGCGCUGGGAUUACAGGUGUGAGCCACCAGGCUUGGCCAAUUAAUUUUUAUUUGAAAAUUAUUUUGGAUUCAGGGGCUAUAUGUGCAUGUUUGUUACAUGGAUAUAUUGCAUACUGCUGGUGUUCAGGCUUCUAUUGAACUCACACUGAUGGAUUUUUAAAAGUCAAAUUAGCCUUGUAUUCCUGGCAUAAACCCCACUUGAUCAUUAUGUAUUAUGCUUUUUAUAUGUCACUGGAUUUGAUUUACUUACAUUUUGUCAAUAAUUUUUGUGUCUGUGUUCAUGAGGCUCUUGUUCUGUAGUUUUCUUUUCUUGUCAUGCCUUUGACUGGUUUUAGAAUGAUGUAAUGUUGGCUUUAUGAAGUGAUUUGGGAAAUAUUCCCUCUUCUAUUUUCUGGUAGAGUUUGUGUAGAAUUGGUAUAUAUUUCUUAAAAGUUUGGUUGAGUUUAUCAUUGAAUUGAUCUGGUCCUUAUUUUUCUAUAUUGGCAGUGUCUUGGUGAGAUUUGGGGCUUUAGAAUCAAGCAACCCCAGAUUAAUAUCUCACUUUGUUAAUUUCUCCCUGUGAGACAUUGGGCAAGUCACACAUUCUCUUUGAGCCUAUUUCCUCAUCUAUCAAAUGGGUAAUUGUGAUAAUUAAAUAAUAAUAUACAUCAUUUAUUCAAUACUCUACUACA